CUCUGUCAGAAUGGCCACCAUGGUACCAUCCGUGUUGUGGCCCAGGGCCUGCUGGACUCUGCUGGUCUGCUGUCUGCUGACCCCAGGUGUCCAGGGGCAGGAGUUCCUUUUGCGGGUGGAGCCCCAGAACCCUGUGCUCUCUGCUGGAGGGUCCCUGUUUGUGAACUGCAGUACUGAUUGUCCCAGCUCUGAGAAAAUCGCCUUGGAGACGUCCCUAUCAAAGGAGCUGGUGGCCAGUGGCAUGGGCUGGGCAGCCUUCAAUCUCAGCAACGUGACUGGCAACAGUCGGAUCCUCUGCUCAGUGUACUGCAAUGGCUCUCAGAUAACAGGCUCCUCUAACAUCACCGUGUACAGGCUCCCGGAGCGUGUGGAGCUGGCACCCCUGCCUCCUUGGCAGCCGGUGGGCCAGAACUUCACCCUGCGCUGCCAAGUGGAGGAUGGGUCGCCCCGGACCAGCCUCACGGUGGUGCUGCUUCGCUGGGAGGAGGAGCUGAGCCGGCAGCCCGCAGUGGAGGAGCCAGCGGAGGUCACUGCCACUGUGCUGGCCAGCAGAGACGACCACGGAGCCCCUUUCUCAUGCCGCACAGAACUGGACAUGCAGCCCCAGGGGCUGGGACUGUUCGUGAACACCUCAGCCCCCCGCCAGCUCCGAACCUUUGGUGAGAGAAGGGGCUUCAGACGGUGGGUGACGAGCUGAGCCAGGGUAGACGGUGCCCUGACCUUGGGGUUCCUGAGAGUGGGGUACCCCGGACCUCACAGGCUUCUGGGAAGGAAAGCCCCCGGCCACUGGGCAAGGUGGCCCCGGAAGGGAGGCCCGAGCCGUGGGAUCUUUGAAGAAGGCCGUUUUCAUGGCCCUGUGUGUGUGUCCUGUGAAGAAGGGUGACCCAGUCAGCAAGAUAUCCUGACUGGGGGGGAUGAGGGUGUCCUGGGGAAGGCACAGUCCUGGGGGUUGUACUAUGCCCACCUUUCUCCCCAGUCCUGCCCGUGACCCCCCCGCGCCUCGUGGCCCCCCGGUUCUUGGAGGUGGAAACGUCGUGGCCGGUGGACUGCACCCUAGACGGGCUUUUUCCAGCCUCAGAGGCCCAGGUCUACCUGGCGCUGGGGGACCAGAUGCUGAAUGCGACAGUCAUGAACCACGGGGACACGCUAACGGCCACAGCCACAGCCACGGCGCGCGCGGAUCAGGAGGGUGCCCGGGAGAUCGUCUGCAACGUGACCCUAGGGGGCGAGAGACGGGAGGCCCGGGAGAACUUGACGGUCUUUAGCUUCCUAGGACCCAUUGUGAACCUCAGCGAGCCCACCGCCCAUGAGGGGUCCACAGUGACCGUGAGUUGCAUGGCUGGGGCUCGAGUCCAGGUCACGCUGGACGGAGUUCCGGCCGCGGCCCCGGGGCAGCCAGCUCAACUUCAGCUAAAUGCUACCGAGAGUGACGACGGACGCAGCUUCUUCUGCAGUGCCACUCUCGAGGUGGACGGCGAGUUCUUGCACAGGAACAGUAGCGUCCAGCUGCGAGUCCUGUAUGGUCCCAAAAUUGACCGAGCCACAUGCCCCCAGCACUUGAAAUGGAAAGAUAAAACGAGACACGUCCUGCAGUGCCAAGCCAGGGGCAACCCGUACCCCGAGCUGCGGUGUUUGAAGGAAGGCUCCAGCCGGGAGGUGCCGGUGGGGAUCCCGUUCUUCGUCAACGUAACACAUAAUGGUACUUAUCAGUGCCAAGCGUCCAGCUCACGAGGCAAAUACACCCUGGUCGUGGUGAUGGACAUUGAGGCUGGGAGCUCCCACUUUGUCCCCGUCUUCGUGGCGGUGUUACUGACCCUGGGCGUGGUGACUAUCGUACUGGCCUUAAUGUACGUCUUCAGGGAGCACCAACGGAGCGGCAGUUACCAUGUUAGGGAGGAGAGCACCUAUCUGCCCCUCACGUCUAUGCAGCCGACAGAAGCAAUGGGGGAAGAACCGUCCAGAGCUGAGUGACGCUGGGAUCCGGGAUCAAAGUUGGCGGGGGCUUGGCUGUGCCCUCAGAUUCCGCACCAAUAAAGCCUUCAAACUCCCUAA